ACAGCCCCGGAGCGCGGCCUGCCGGGGAGGUGGAUCUCGCGCUCCCCACACAGUCACACUCCGCGCACUCACACACUUGGAAGCGCCUCCCCACGUCCCUCCCCUGCCCUCCUCUUGCUCUGCUCUUCUCUCCCUCACCACAAAUAGUCGCCGACCUACUGCCAAUCCGCCUCUCCUCUCUCUCUCUCUCUGUCUCAACAUGACUGACUGGGAAGCGGUGGCUCGGGCAGAGCAGCUCCGCUGGCGCAGGCAGGAGGAGCAGGAGGAUUAUUAAAUAACGCAGCUGGACUCUGUGCAACUGGGAGUGGAGAGGAGCCCAACAGCCGAGAAGGGGAGGGAGGGCAGAGGAGGGGGACCAGGAAGGACACCCCCGUGCCCCGAAGACAUAAAUCCCUGAGUGCCCGGGAGGAGCCUUAACAAGCGCACGGAGCCCUCAAGGCUGCAAAGUUGGCUUUCACAGUGCAAGCCUUUGAUUCCCAAUGGGGGACUCAGGAUCAAGACGAUCUACCCUGGUCUCCCGGUUGCCAAUAUUCAGAAGAAGUAUUAACAGAAGACAUGAUUCUCUUCCUUCUUCACCUUCUUCCAGUAAUACAGUUGGUGUCCACAGUUCCUCUCCUUCCAGCACUAACUCAAGCUCAGGUAGCACAGGUAAACGGAGGAGCAUAUUCCGUACUCCUUCCAUUAGCUUCCACCAUAAGAAGGGGAGUGAGCCUAAGCAAGAGCCUACCAACCAGAACCUUAGUAUUUCAAAUGGUGCUCAACCUGGUCACAGCAAUAUGCAGAAACUGAGUUUGGAAGAACAUAUUAAGACCAGGGGAAGACAUUCUGUUGGUUUUAGUAGUUCACGAAAUAAGAAGAUAACAAGAUCUUUGACAGAGGAUUUUGAAAGGGAAAAAGAGCACUCAACUAACAAGAAUGUCUUUAUAAAUUGUCUAAGUUCUGGCAAAAGUGAAGGGGAUGAUUCUGGUUUCACAGAAGACCAAACUCGUCGUUCUGUUAAGCAGUCAACAAGGAAGCUACUCCCUAAAUCUUUUUCAUCUCACUAUAAAUUUUCUAAGCCAGUUCUACAGAGCCAAUCCAUUUCAUUGGUACAACAGUCUGAAUUCUCAUUGGAAGUUACACAGUACCAAGAGAGAGAACCUGUAUUAGUAAGAGCUUCGCCAUCCUGUUCUGUGGAUGUAACAGAACGGGCAGGAAGCUCUUUACAAUCUCCUUUGCUUUCUGCUGAUCUUACCACAGCUCAGACACCUUCAGAAUUUUUAGCCUUGACUGAAGAUUCUGUGUCUGAAAUGGAUGCAUUUUCUAAAAGUGGAAGCAUGGCAUCCCACUGUGACAACUUUGGCCACAAUGAUUCUACCUCUCAGAUGUCCCUCAAUUCUGCUGCUGUUACAAAGACAACAACAGAACUUACGGGAACUGUUCCCUGUGCAAUUAUGUCUCCUGGGAAAUAUAGGUUAGAGGGUCAAUGUAGCACUGAAUCUAAUUCAUUACCGGAAACCUCUGCUGCUAAUCAGAAGGAAGUGUUAUUACAAAUUGCUGAACUACCUGCUACAAGUGUGAGCCACUCAGAGAGUAACCUACCAGCAGAUAGUGAAAGAGAAGAAAAUAUAGGGUUACAAAAUGGUGAAACAAUGCUGGGGACAAACUCCCCAAGGAAACUUGGAUUUUAUGAGCAACAUAAAGCAAUAGCGGAACAUGUAAAAGGGAUCCAUCCUAUUUCAGAUUCAAAGAUAAUACCUACUUCUGGUGAUCAUCAUAUUUUUAACAAAACAUCACAUGGAUAUGAAGCAAAUCCUGCCAAAGUUCUUGCCAGUAGUCUCAGUCCAUUUCGUGAAGGAAGAUUUAUAGAGAGGAGACUGCGAUCCUCGUCAGAAGGCACUGCAGGGAGUAGCAGAAUGAUUUUGAAACCGAAAGAUGGAAAUAUAGAAGAAGUUAAUAGUUUAAGAAAGCAAAGAGCAGGUUCUUCAUCUUCAAAAAUGAACAGUUUGGAUGUUUUGAAUAAUUUGGGAUCUUGUGAACUGGAUGAAGAUGAUCUAAUGCUUGAUCUUGAAUUUUUAGAGGAACAGAGUCUUCACCCUUCUGAACUACCGCAGGAACAUACCAGGAAAGCCAAGAGAAUCCACAGACCUUUGAAGGAAUUGGAUCACCGCCACAGGCUCCCUGAGAUGGCAAAAAACUUUUGCCGGGAGGACUCAUAUCACUCUGUCGUCUCAUGUGCCGCAGUAGUUCUUACUCCUAUGGAACCAAUGAUAGAAAUGAAGAAAAGAGAAGAACCAGAAUUUCCUGAGCCUUCCAAACAGAAUCUUUCCCUGAAAUUAACAAAGGACGUUGAUCAAGAAGCCAGGUGUUCCCACAUCAGCCGAAUGCCCAACAGUCCAUCUGCGGAUUGGCCUCUACAAGGUGUGGAAGAAAACGGAGGCAUAGAUUCUCUGCCAUUCAGACUGAUGUUACAGGACUGCACGGCAGUCAAGACGUUAUUAUUAAAGAUGAAGAGAGUUCUUCAAGAGAGUGCAGACAUGAGUCCAGCAAGCAGUACCACGUCACUUCCUGUUAGUCCUCUUACUGAAGAGCCAGUGCCUUUCAAGGAUAUAAUGAAAGAUGAAUGCUCGAUGCUCAAGCUGCAGCUGAAAGAGAAGGAUGAACUCAUUUCCCAACUUCAGGAAGAGCUGGGAAAAGUCCGGCAUUUACAGAAGGCUUUUGCUUCAAGAGUAGAUAAAUCCACACAGACUGAACUACUAUGCUAUGAUGGUUUAAACUUGAAAAGACUAGAGACAGUACAAGGAGGGAGAGAGGAGAGCAAGAUGAUAAGAAUAUGGUCAUCAGUAUGACUGGGGAAAAAAGGCACUUCAUAAGGAAGAUCUCAGAACCUUUUACAGCUUUGUGAGAAUGACUGCUUUCAUUCAGAUGUAACCAAAAUGGAUCUACUUAUAGAAAGAACUAAACUGAUCACCUCCUAAAGUGAAAGUUUUCAUCCGAGCAGUACUGCUACAAUUUAUUUCUGCUGAUUUAGUGCCUUUAGGGACAUACUAAGUGGAGUUACUCGGCUUCUCCUUGCUGCUUCCUGGUCUAAUAGCAACUUUGUGUCAAAAGAAGGAAAACUGAAAUCUAUAUAUCCGUACGAUGGCAUUGCUAAAUGGUGCCAAAUUCUGCAUUUGUUUUACUAAGAUUUUUAUAGUUUUUAAUGUUAUUUUUAAAUGCAUAAUGAUUGGGUUUUAUUGAAAGAGUGGCUCUUAAAUCAUAUUGCUUAUUUUUCUAACGUCCUUUGAUUUUAUUUUUAUUAUAAGUGUACUUAUAAGUAAGGAACAUGGUAAAAUGUGUUUAAAUUAAUUUUAGAAGUAUAUUGUUCUCAAAACUAUUUUGUGAUUUCUCUGAAGGUCAAAAUUGUAAUAAUUUACAAUUUAAUGUAUACAUCUCCAUAGAAGGGACAACACUGAUUUUGGCCUUCUCCCUCAGGGUAGUGGAAUAAUUGUAAAAAGCUAAGAUCAUCAAAUUAACCAUAAUCCAGUAAUGUCUUCUGCACUUGACAUCUCUAAUUCAUGACCAGAAAGUAAAUGUCAACUAUUAAAAUUCAAAACAACUACUUAACUUCCACUUAGGGCAGCACUGGGUUACUUAAGCAUAUUUCUAUUCAAUGUAACUACUUACCUUAACUUUCCCUGUGACUAAGAGGCCUAGUAUGUUCUAAGAUAAGAAACUUCAGGGAGGUAUAAGACAAUUAGGUGAAGUAUGUUGUAAAAACUGUUCUUUUCAAGUCUCAAUGGUAGAUGACCUGUAAACAAAGAGUACAAUUACUAUGUUAAGGACCUUGUGAUCUCACUUGCUUAAGAAAUGGGACGUGUAUGUAUCUAAUUUCCAUUUGUUAUGUUCUAGGAUGUGUGUGCAUAACAAGAUGUACAAUGUAAUUCUGAUUAUGUUAAAUUGAAAUGUGAGGGUUUAGAAAACUCUUACUCCAAAUGAUUUCUUAGAAUUUCUCAUUGUAAUGCUAUUAUGAUUGAUAAAUGACAAUAAUUGUUUAUUAUGAUGAAUUAAUUUCUUAGUUCAAAUGACAGCUAUUCCCCAUAGGUGUUGAUGGAUGCAAUAUCAAGGGCUUAUUACCAAAUAUUUAUAAGAAGAUUUAAGAAGUGUCAUUUAAAAUAUUCUAUUUACUUAUUGAAGUAAUGAAAACAGAGUAUUCAUAGAAAAUGAAGUAGACAGUAAUAUGCUAUUUAGCUAAGUGGUAAAUACCAUUAAAAAACGAAUUGCCAGACAGGAAGGCUAGAUUUGAAACUAUAUGCUGUAUAAAAAUAUAAGUUAAGGAGAAGUGAUUAAAAUGUAAAUUACUUUUCUGAAGGAAAUAGAGAUAGGUAACACCUAAAUUGCUAAAUUGUGAAAUAUACAAAAAUAGUUAUUAGCUGUAUGAAAUAACCCCAUUUAUAUUGGUAUUUUUACAUUUUUAUACGUGCAUAUUGUGUAUACAAUUUGAGGGGGCUGAUUAUAAUAGAUAAUAAAAAGCUUGUUUAAAAAGGGAGAUUAGUAGAAUGCUAUACAAAAUGUGAUUGUUUAACAGAUAUUUCUAACUGAUUAUAAACAAUUUUCUUGCAUCCAGUGGGAUUUUGCAACUCAUAGAAAAACCUCAGUGAAAUUCACUGGGUAAGACACAUAGAUAAGUCAUUUUUUUUUUCAUUAAGUGUGGAUAAUACUAAGUUACUGUAAUUUUUCUUAAAAGACUUUAAAAUACCUUUGUUAUUUUAGGUAGUUUUUUUGUUUUCCAAAGGCCAGUUUUUGUUUAAGUAUUAAAGCUUCUGUGUGUGCCUGUAGCAGGACGAGCCAUGGACAAAACCCCACAGACACCGAGGUAGUGAAGGAAGUAGCUUUUAAUCAGCUGAAAGCAUCAGCAGACUAGCAUCCUAAAAUCCGAGCUUGUUGAGUGCACAAUUUCUGUCCCUUUUGAGGGCUCAUAACACUAAAGAUUUUACAUGAAAGGGCCGUGAUUGAUUGAACAAUCUAGGCGGUAUGUGACAGGGGCUGCAAGCACCAGCAAUCAGAGUGAAACAGAACAGAAUGAGAAGCUUCAGAGUGUCCUUCCAUACAAUGUCUGGAAUCUGUGGAUAAUAUCGGUUGCUAGGUCAUGGGUUGAAUUUUAACUAUCAGGCUAAGGUCAGGCAGGCCCAGGCCUGGUUUUGGGUCUGGUGCCUGGCUCUGGGCUGCCUGCCUUUGGUUUCACUUCCUUGUUUCUUCUUAAAGCAGGUACUGAAUAUAAAACAAUAUAAAACAAUAUGGGGGGAUCUCUUUCUCUCUUCUUUCAUUUCCCACCUUUGAGACUCUCACUCAUUUUAUUAGUGGGAAUUCUCACUUUCAUUUUCACUACUUAUGUCUUCCCGUGCAAUAGAUUGAUAGUGAUUCAUAUAAUAUACUUGUGCUGAAGCAUUCUGGUGAACUAAGGUAAUGAUGAAGCUUUUUAUCAUUUGAAGAAGUACAGGUAGCAAACAAGGGAGUAGUAAGCAGGUUCCUAUUACUAUUAUAACUCCUAUGAUAAGAGUUUUAAAUCCUCCUAUUGCUGGGAACCAAUUUCCAAACAUGGCCCCAGGAUCAAAUCCGUGCCACACUUGCAUGGGUACAUGUGCCAGUUUUGUUAUAUCUUUAAAUAUGUCUUCAACUACUUGCCCUUGAUCAUCUAUGUGGAAACAGAAAUUAGUAAGGUUAAAUUUUCCACAAACUCCUCCUUCAGCUGCUAGCAAGUAGUUCAGAACUAGUCUAUUUUGGUAGAUAGUAUUCCUUAUCUGAGUCUCUUGCUGGGCAAGAACAGUCAAGACUUGACAGGUUUUAUUAGUAAUAAUUUCUAAAACAGCUUGCAACCGUAUGAUUCAGUUGAGCAUGAAGAUGGGGGUCCGAUAUCCCCAUGAGCCAUCUUGUGCCCAAGUGGUGGGUCCACAGUAUUGUAUAAUUCUUUCAGGGGGCCAUUCAUCAUCUUUCCAGUUACCUAUGGCUAUGCUUCAUUUUUCGCGGGAAGCAUAGACAGGGAAUCCUAGGAGUUUGUCUGUUUUUAUGGGCAGUAGGAAGAAAGGUGGUGUAAUAGUGCCAAUUACACAGCUACCUGUCCACUGAUCAGGUGGCUUAGCAUAGGCUCUAUGUCCACAUAUCCAGUAUAACCUGCUGGGGGCAAUCCAGUCCUGGCGGAAUUCUGGGUGGGCUCAAACAGUCUGCAAUUUUGGAAAUUUACUGAAUGGAUUUCUUUCUGUGUAAUUGGAACUCCACCAUGUAACUGUUUUUGUGGUACCAUUAUACAGUUUUUGUCCAAGACACCUAAGCCUUACUACAGGAUGAGUGAAUUCUUUUCCUUCUCUAGCUAUGCAAUAUUGUCCAAUAAUUGAGGCUUUUAGAACCCAGAAAUUGUCAGGGUGGUUCUUUUGGGCUGGGAAUUCAUCAGGAACUGGGUCUGCAGGAACUAAUUCUUGGGCUUCCCAUGGCCACUGAUCUCCUGUUACAGUUCCUCCACAAACAUACCAUUAAGUGACUUAGACACUGAGCUACAUGCUCGGCUAAUUGCAAAAACAAAUUUCUAGUUUUUCCUGGAAUUUCAGGUACUGGCACAUUUAGUUCAUCAUAGAAAGUCUGAAAUACUGGCUCUGGAGAGCAUUUUCGAAUCUCUCCUUUUAUUAAAAUAUUUACCUCAGGGUCUAGUCCUUUUCCAUCAAUGCCUGGAGAUACGUACUCUCCUUUUCUCCAUUUUGGGUCCAAGGGGUUUGUGAUUACUAAUUCUUAAAGGUUGCAGCUUCCACUCAUGCAGGAGGGGCUUCCUUUCCCUUUUUGGAGCCAAACAGGAUCUUCUUCAUCCUUUUCCCAAGUAGCCCAAAUGACACAUGACCAGUACCCACAUUUUUUUCCACACAAUCCUACAGAUGUACUUAUUUUCGGUCAUGUAUCUUUUUUCCCAAUUAAAAGAGCCACAUCCUGCUCCUAGCUUAUUUCUAUUAAUGACAGCACAAGCGUCAAAUUAUAAGAUUAUGCGUUUGGGCACCCCUUUUUCUUCUGUUCUGGCUAAUACUUUACUUGUAUCAUUUAUGAGUCCUCACUAGUCUUCAGUCCUUAAUCUGAUUUCAAAAACUAUGGAAAUGGGAGGUUCAGAGGGGUCAUAGCACACGUCGGGCUGGUCACUUCCUGGAUUACAGACUUUGUACUGAGUGUUAUUAUACAAACAUGUUCCUUUUGGAAUUACUAGGCAUUCAUAAUAACUAUAGAACAAAAAAAAUUGUCUUAACGUGUUGUCCUACCUCAGUGACCUGAUAUAUGCACUGAAAGCAGUCCUCUGUGUGGGAAGAAGCAGUGGAAGCUUUUACCACACCAGUCCAUGUUAUAAGGAAAAUAAGUCCCACGACUAUUUUCCUCAUGCUUCAGCCAUGCGUAGACCAGUCAGCUUCCGGGUGUGACUGGAGCAGGGCUUGUCGUCCUCCUCAGGGUUACUUUGCAGGGAUUGUCUAGGCUUGGUUUGGCCUCCCAGGUUCCAGUGGCUGCGGGCUUUAUGUGGCUGUGGUGAAUCCAGGCUGGAAUUCCUUCUACCUUCACAGCUGUGGGAGUGGUCAGGAUAACGGUCUUGGGUCCCUUCCACUGUGGCCGUAAGGGAGCUACAUUUCAGUCCUUGAUCCACACACGGUCACCUGGAGAAAAAGGGUGAACUGGGGAGAAUAAGCUGACUGAGCACCUCUCAUUUACCCAAGUUGAGAUUGUCUGGGUAAUUUUCCCCAAGGCCUGUAACUGUCUCUGCAAUUCAAUUUCAUCCAACUCUUGGGGAGUACCUGGAAGUCCUCGCGGUAUAGGAGGAGGCCUAUGAUAUAAUGUUUCAUAAGGGGAGUAUCCUGUUUUCUUAGAGGGGGUGCACCUAAUUUUAAAUAAUACCAUAGGAAGGGCCUGUAUCCAUUUUAAUCCUGUCUCUUGAUAUACUUUCCCUAAACUAUUUUUGAUAGUCUGAUUCAUUUGCUCCACCUUUCCGGAACUGUGAGGUUGGUAGGCGGCAUGUAGCUUCCAAGUGAGUCCCAAUACCUUUGCUGUCCUCUGUACUAAGUCAGCCACAAAUGCUGGCCCAUUUUCUGAGCCAAUCCGUAGAGGCAGUCCAAACCUAGGGAUGAGAUCUCAAAGAAGCACAUGGGUUACUUCAUGAGCUUUUUCAGUUCAUGUUGGAUAAGCCUCUACCCACCCAGAGUAAGUACACACUAGAACCAGUAAAUACUUGUUACCUCUGCAUUUGGGCAUCUCUGUGAAGUCCAUUUGAAGAUCUUCAAAGGGAGCUGCUCCAUAGGCUUGUAUGCCAGGAGGAACAGAGGGGCCUUGCUUUGCAUUGUGCUGUCGACAGGUAACACAUUGCUGUGCUGCUGUUUUAGCAAGAGCUGGCAAGUGUGAGAUGUAGAAAUACUGGCUGAACAGCUUUUCAAGUGACUCCUGGCCUAAAUGGGUAGUUUCAUGUACAGCCAGCAUGACUGCAGCUCCUAGCAGCUGUGGCACAGCUAUUCUUCCAUCUGGUAACUGUAUCCACCCUUCUUUUAUUGUUUGUCCUCCCUCUGCCUGAAGAAAGUCUUUUUCCUCUUUAGAAGAAGUAGGCACCAGAUCAGGUGUUUGAGGGAGUAGGGGGGCUGUGACUGAUGCCCGGUAAGGAGUAGAUGCUGCUUUUCCUGCCUCUGUGUCUGCUCAGGGGUUUCCUUGGCUCACUGAGGUGGAAGCUCACUGGUGUCCCUUGCAAUGCAUGACUGCCACCUUUUGGGGUUUCCAUACUGCCUCUAAUAAUUGUAGAAUUUCUUGUUGAUAUUUUAUGUCCUUUCCCCCGAAUUUAAUAGGCCUUUUUCUUUAUAUAAUGCUCCAUAUACUUGAAUGGUUAGAAAGGCAUAUCAAGAGUCAGUAUAAAUGUUUACAGUCUUACCUUCACUAAGUUCUAGAGCCCGAGUUAAAGCAAUGAGUUCUUCCUUCUGGGCUGAAGUGCCCUGAGGCAAUGGUUUGGCUUCAAUAACAUCAUCCAAAGUUACCACCGCAUAUCCUGCGCAUCUUUCUCCUCGUGGACUGAUGAAGCUGCUCCCAUCCACGUAUAACUCCCAGUCCACUGAUGCCCAUGACUGGUCUCGAAGAUCGAGUCUGCUAGAAUACACUGAGUCCAACACUUCCACACAGUUAUGUUCAACAGGGCUGUCUGAUACUGGGAGUAAGGUUGCAGGAUUCAGAGCGUUACAGACCUCAAUGGUUAUGCGGGGGUUUUCACAUAGCAAGCUUUGGUACUUGGUUAAUCUAGCAUUUGUUAGCCCAUGGUGUCCUUUGGUAUUUGUUAAAGUCACCACCACAUGGGGGACCUUUAUACUUAAGUUUUGCCCAAGGGUUAGCUUGUCUGCUUCUUAUGCUAACAGGACUGUAGCUGCCAGGGCUCUCAGACGUGGAGGCCAGCCUUUUGAAGCUCCGUCUAGCUGUUUUGAGAGGUAGGCCACUGGUCUUGGCCAGGGCCCCACAGUUUGGGUUAAAACUCCAACUGCCAUUUUUUCUCUUUCUGACACAUAGAGUGUAAAGGGCUUUGUCAAAUCUGGUAGUCCUAAGGCUGGGGCUGACAUAAGUUUUUCCUUUAACUUGCAAAAGUCUUGCUGUUGCAGAGGUCCCCAUUCAAAAGGCUCCCAGUUGCCCCCCUUUGUAACCCCAUACAACGGUUUGGCUAGCACUGCAAAGUUUGGAAUCCAUAAUCUGCAAAACCCCACAGAUCCUAGAAAUUCCCUUACUUGCCUUCUGGUUUUAGGUUUCGGUAAGCUGCAGAUGACUUGCUUUCUUUCUGACCCCAGGCUGUGCUUCUCUUUCCGAAUAGUGAAUCCCAGGUAGCGUACCUGCUGUCUGCAGAUCUGAGCUUUCUUCUUGGACAUCUUAUACUCACAGUCCUCCAGGUGUCGAAGCAGGGCAUCCGUCCCUUUGGCAUACCCAUCUGCCGUGGAGUGUCCUAGCAGAAGAUUGUCCACGUACUGGAGCAAGACACAGCCUAGGUCUUUAGCAGGAAACUUCUGGAGGUCUCGAGCCAACACCUCCCCGAAGAUGGUGGGGUAAUUUUUAAACCCCUGGGGAAGCCGAGUCCAAGUGUACUGAGUAGUAACACCUGACCCCGGAUCUUCCCACUGAAAGGCAAACAGCUUUUGGCUCUCAGGAGCUAGUCUGAUGCUAAAGAAGGCAUCCUUCAAGUCCAGACAAGUGAACCAGCUGUCCUCAGCUGGCAGCAAUCCUAACAGUGUGUAAGGGUUAGGAACUGUUGGGUGUAGAGUCACUGUAGUUUGGUUAACCAAGCGUAAGUCCUGUACAGUUCGAUAGUCCUUGGUCCCUGGCUUGGGGACAGGUAGGAGGGGGGUGUUCCAUGGAGAUUGUCAAGGAACUAUAAUCCCAAAAGCUUUCAAGCAUGUAAGAUGAACCUGUAUUCCUUCAAGAUCUUCUCUGGGAACCGGAUACUGCUUUUGUCUAAUUGGCUGAGCCCCAGGCUUAACUUGUAUGAGUACUGGGGCUUGAUUGAUCGUCAGCCCUGGAGGAUUGUCCUCCGCCCAUACUCAGGGCCAUCGCUUAGCUAGAGCCGGUUUUAUCUCCUGACCUGGCUCGGUUAGAAAAAGUCUCCAUUCUUCUUCUCAGGGGACUGUAAGGGCCAUGAUAACUCCUGUUCCUGGUAACUUCAGUUGUAAAGAGCCCUGUUUUGUAAAGGAAAUGGUGUCUCUCAGCUUACUAAGCAAGUCUCUCCCUAAAAAGGCAAGGGGCAAUCAGGUAUAUACAGAAAUUGAUGAGUCACUUUAUGUCCUCCCACUGAGCAGGUCCAAGGUAGGCAGAAAACCUGCUUGGCGGAGACUCCCGUUGCUCCAAUUAUAUCAAUGGUUUUUUUGAUAAGAGGGCCACUGGGGUGGUUACUACUGAGUGUCCGGCACCAGUAUCAACCGAAAACUUAAUGUCCUUGCCCCCUAUUGUCAUCCUGACCAUGGGCUCCUUGGAGGCAUUUGAGCCCGGUCCCCUUCAGUCUAGUAGCCCUUCGAACAGAUUGAACAAAGUCCCUUCGUCUUUAUCUGUGGUCUUUUGCUGUGCGUCACCUUGCUUCUCCUUUAGUUGGAGACACUUAUCUUUCCAAUGUCCUAUUUCUUUACAGUAGGCACACUGGUUACACUGCACAUGUGAGUGAUUGGACUGGGCAUUCCUCCUGGAACCCCCCUUUCCCUGCCCUUUGGGGGGGAUCCCUCUAAUUGCCACAGCCAGCAAAUCAGUGUUCUGCCUGGCCUGGCCUUCACCCUCCUUAUGGCUUUCUCAGCGGCUUGUUACAUCUCUAUUUACAAAUACUUGAUCAGCUAUCUCCCGUAACUGCGAGGUAUUCAUCUCUGCAAAAACAGCCUGUUUUUGCGAUUUCCUCCGGAUAUCUUCCAUGCUUUGGCUAACUAAGGCCAUGUUAAUCAUAUGCUGAUUUUCAGGACUAUCCGGAUCAAAAGGAGUGUACAUACGAUAGGCCUCACACUGUCUUUCAUAGAAUUGGUCUGGGCUUCCCUCCUUUCCUUGGAUGACUUCAGAAACUUCAUUUACAUUGGUGGCCUUCUGAGCCCCUUUUUUCAGCCCUUCAAUUAAUGCCUCCCAGUAUCGUUUUAACCUCUCCAUAUCUGGUCCUUCAUUUGGAUCCCAUUGAGGGUCUGUUCCUGGCAGAACAAUUCUUAUGUAUUCCUGAGGAUUUUGGUAAUCAGCUGGGACAUGGUCCUCUAGCCAUUUAGUUGCCACCUGGAGUAUCCUUCACCUUUCAUCUGUGUUAAAGAUGUACAUGAGUAGCUGGUGGUGAUCAGCCCAAGUAGGAUUAUGAGUCUGUAUAAUAGUUUGGAGCAAGUCAAUUAGAGCUUCAGGCUUUUCAGUGUAAGAUGGAAUAUUAUUUUUCCAGUUGAGGAGGUCAGCAGAGGUGAAAGGGUAAUAUAAAAAGCACACCUUUCCACUGUAUGUCCAUCCUCAUCUAUCCCAGCAUAUUGCUGCUUUCUCAGGGGCAUUUGGAUUCCAGUAUUGGGCCGUAAAUGGGCCGCCAAGGGAGGAGUUUCUCCUGCAGCUUCUCUUCCUUUCUUGUCUACUCUGUGUGGUCUAGGGGCUGUGGGCUCAGGAGUAGGGGGCCUUUCCACUUGGUAAAGGUGGGGCACUGUUGGUGCCAUCUCCUGCCAUGAGUCUUCAGGCUCUGAAUCAGACAGAACUUUAGGGGCUGGCUUCCCUCGGCAGGUGGAGUGAGAACUUUCCUUAACUAACUGUCCCUUUGCUACUAGUACUGCUGCUGCCUGUCCCCUUAACCACUAUGGGGGAUCUAAAACUAGCUGUAACCAGGAAUCUAUAUAUGGGAACUGAUCUGGGUGUCCUGGCUUGCCAGUUACUUUAUGCCAUACCUUUGAAACCAGAGACCUGUCCAGGCUUCCUUCUGAUGGCUAACUUACCUCUAAUUCGGGCCAAUCUAUUUCACACAAAGUUCUUAGUUUUCCUGGAGUCAUAGUGACUCCAUAGUCUCCUUUGAAUCCUUUCUUGAAAUUAUUUAACAUAGUUCCCAAUGGAGUGGGCUUACAUUUUGCCUGGCCCAUGUUUUCUGAAGACAAAAUAUCAUGCUCACACCACACACUCACCACAAAACAAAGAACAGGUAAAGAGGGCACACACACACCUUUAUCGUUUAUACCAAAACAAAAUCAGAGUACCAAGAAAUUCAAGCCAAGUCAAAACCAAAACCAAAGUAUCAGGCAAUUCAAGUCAAGUCAAAACCAGAACAGAAGUGCCGACACAGGCACACCGUGGGUGAUCAGGCCACGCUUCCACUUAAAUGGAGUGGGCAAGUUUCAAAGACAUGUCUUACCAAGUUUCAGAUGUCCGGACUCCAAGUGCCAGGUCCUUCCCAGUGUCCAGCCGGUGCCUGUGUGCACAGUUUUUUAAUGGCGGAUUGUCUUUAUUUUUACCCUACCUCAAAAAUGCCCAACCAUCGGUAUUCUGAAUAUUCUGUAUCACAGGUCUAAAAUCACAUGAUAUGUGACUUUAUAUCAUGAUGAAGAGAACUAAUAAUUAUGGUUGAAUAUCUAAAUCAGGAAUAAAUAUUUAGCUUCUGAAAUUCUAUUGAAUGUGAUAAGCUAAUAUGAAAGACACUGGCUAUUGGAACUUUUGGAUUAAGGCUGUUAUUGGAAGUUACAGAAACUCAGGAACCAUAGAGGCUAUGCAAAUGAAGUACAAAUGUGUAGUGAUCAAGGAUCACUUUUAUAUAAUUUGCAUGACUCAGAUCUCUUAAAGUGAUGAACAGUCUUGGCAGGGAUAAUGUUGAUCUUAUUAAUCUGAAAUUCUGAAAAAAGGUUAAUAUUGGUACACUUGAAUAUUUUAGAUAGUUUAUACUCUUAUAAAACUGAUUAUAAAAAUGCUUCUUAAACAUCAGAAAGAGAAUUAACACUUUAGAUAAUUUCUAGAAGUAUUUAGAAAUAUGAUCAAUAACUUUAUAGACAUACUCAUUCCAUUACUGCAAAAAUCCCCGCUUGUGUUUUGGAAAUUUUUCAGUUGAUGAUAUUUGUGUGAUCAUGCCAUUGAUAUUUAAAAAUCCCACUUUUGUUUGUGGGAUUGCAAGUACAGAUAGAUUCUUAUAGACACUUAGGAAAAAAGUGUACAUUUUAAAUUAUUAAAAUAGAUGAUUUAUGAAUGUAUCAUUCUCAAGAAAAUAAUGAGCAUAUCUUAUAACCUGUUAUCUGUUUUAGAGUCCAGAAUGCUUCACUAACUUUCUCUGCUGGAUUACAGUGUGCUGAUUCUCCAUUUUCUUUGCUGAAAACCAUAAAUAGGAAAUUACUGAUGAUACAAACCUCAGAGACUUAAAGAAACAUAAUUAGAGACAGUUGAAAAAGGCAGAUUGAAAAUCAAUGUUUAGUUAAGUACUCUUUUCCCAGCCCUGUUUUAUAUUUACAUUCAUUAAUCAUUGAAAAUAAUACUUCAAGAUUCUUUAUUGAUGUAAAGUAUCAUUUGAAUAUAUAACAUCCUAAAGAAAGGAAUUAUUUUAUUCUGAUAGUGGACUUUAUGCCUUUGCUAAUAGACUUGGAUAGACUUUGCAUUGUUUAUCUUUUGAGGAAUUAAAUAUUUCUACUUGAAAUUGAAAAUCAUUUUAAUUCUCUCCAAAAGAGAAAAUUCUGAGAAUCAGAUAAAUUAUAUUCUGAAUUUCAAAGUAACUUGCCAACCUGCAACAUUAGCACAAGAAUGAUUUCAACUGGAACAAAAUAAAAAUCACAAACAAUUUCUCUUUCCAUUUAUAACUUAAUUAGAAUUAUGAAUCAGACUACUUUAGGACUAGGUUAUUGCUUGAGUUAAGCAAAGUCACUCUUUUCUCUUGCCCAAAAGAUCACUGGAGAUAAUUUUUUUUUUUUUUUGAGAUGGAGUCUUGCUGUGUUGCCCAGGCUGGAGAGCAGUGGUGUGAUCUCUGCUCACUGCAAGCUCCGCCUCCCGGGUUCAUGCCAUUCUCCUGCCUCAGCCUUCUGAGUAGCUGGGACUACAGGCAUGUACCACCACGCCCAGCUAAUUUUUUGUAUUUUUAGUAGAGAUGGGGUUUCACCAUGUUAGCCAGGGUGGUCUGGAUCUCCUGAUGUCGUGAUCUGCCCGCCUCGGCCUCCCAAAGUGCUGGGAUUACAGGCGUGAGCCACCGCGCCCAGCUGAGAAUUGUUUUUUUAAAGGGAUAAAAGAAGAAAAAUACACAACUUCCAAGACUAGAACUAAAAUUGAAGAAAAUGUACUAUUCUUGGAAAUAAGAGUUAGCAAAAAUCAUUAAGCACUAUUGUUCCCUUAAGGUCUAGUAUUUUGUAUAAUUUGGAAAUUAUAGGAGAUAACUAUACUUAUUUUAUAGCCUUGUGCAUUGAAUAAAAAGAAUCUUCCAUAAGAAAUUGAUCAUGAUUACAAGUUUUCUUUGAUAAUUUUUGUGCAAAACUUGCUUCUACUUGUAUGUUUUCUUUAUGGUCUAAUAUGCAGAAUACACUAUCUUGAAUUUUUCUACUUCAGUUCAACUUUAGAGAUCCCAUUCUUAGUUUCUGUAUAGUUUAGUAGAAUAAGAAAAUCUUGUAUAAUAUCAGUGAUGACAAUUUUUUGGGAAAUAUAUAGAAUUUUUCAGUGGUUUGGUGCCUAUAGCCCACCACUAAGAUGUAUCUGAUGAACAGUGUGAAUUUAAGAUCAAGAGACCCUUUAAGGACUCAGUAAAAAAUAUCUCAAAACUCAGAAUUGAUAGGCAAUAAGGAGAGUAAACGAUCUUUAUACUUAUUGUCAAUGAAAAGGGUCAAACUCUGUAAAAUAUUUGAAGAGAUUUAUUCUGAGCCACAUGAGUGACCAUGGUCCAUGACAUAGCCCUCAGGAGGCCCUGAGAACACAUGUCCAAGGUAGUUGGGGCGCAGCUUGGUUUUUUACAUUUUAGAGAGGCAUGAGACAUCAAUCAAAUACAUUUAAGAAAUACAUUGGUUUGGUCCAGAAAGGUGGGACAACUCAAAGCAGGGGGUGGGGUGGGGACUGCUUCCAGGCUAUGGGUAAAUUUAAACAUUUUCUGUUUGACAAUUGGUUGAGCUUAUCUAAAGACCUGGGAUGACAGAAAGGAAGUGUUCAGGUUAAGAUAAAAGACUGUGGAGACCAAGGUUCUUUUGAGGUCUUAUAGUGGCUGCUCUUAGAGACAAUAGAUGACAAGGGUUUCCUAUUCAGAUCUUUAAAAGGUGCAGACUUAGUUAAUCUCUUUAGGCUUGGGAGGGCCAGGAAGAAAAAAAACUAGCUAUGUUAGUAGAGAUUCUUUACAGAUGCUGAUUUUCCUCCACAAAAGACAGCUUUGCAGGGCCAUUUCAAGACAUGGCAAAGAAACAUGUUUUGGGGUAAAAUAUUUUGAUUUUCUUCCUUGUCUUGUAAUGUUAUGCCAGAGUCAGGUUGGAAAGUAAGUCACAAUAUAUAGAGUUAAAUAAAACCCAUCUGAUGAGAAUUUAUGAUUUGUAGGGCAUGACUCCCCAGACCCUUUAUAUAGGAAUUUGGGCAAGAUAAAAAAAAAAUCAGUUUGGUCCUCAUUAUAAAUCAACAUUUAAUUAAAAGAACUACACAUUACAAGACCAUAAUAAUUGUUCCUGUUUCAAAAGUUUGUUGAGAAAAUGAGUUAAUAUGCAUAAAGCUCUUUGAGUAGUGUCUGGCACAUAGGAAGCACCCAAUACAUGGCAACAGUUACUAUUAUUAUUAUUAUUAUUUAUAUAAUCAGGUCUUUCCUUCAUAUUUUCUUCUGUCAGAGAGUGUUUGAGUGUCAUGCUAUUCAGAGAUUUUACUGUCUGCGUUGACUAGUCCACACCAUGACAAUCAAUGAUAUCCUAUGCCAGGUCUGAUUUUUAAAGGAUUUUACAUUCCAAAUCGGUUCUGAGGUAGCAAAUCCCAAAUAUGGCAAAAAAUUCUACUUUGGAAUCUUUAUUUAACCUCAAAUAUUCUAUUUCCACAUGUUAUAUUACAGAUGAGAGAAAAAAUAUUUACCUUUUCUACUUAUGGCAUUGUUUAUUGAAGGCAGUGCUUAAGGACUAUAGGUUUUGUAAGCUGUUUUUCACAUCCUAUAUAUGUUCUGGGUCAUCUUCAGAUUGGAUUUUGAAGAUCUCUUCUAUGUUUGUAGAUCACUGACCUUCCAAGAAAUGACCUCAAAGAAACCUGUUGAUCAAGCAAAACUAAGCUUAGUAGAUCUACUUCAGUAAGAAAGAUCACAGUAGUGUCUCAAAUGGGGAAAAAAAUAACAGUACACUCAGUUUAACUUUUUUCUUCUUCUUUGGAAGUGUUUGACUGGUUAUCUGGAUCAGAUAUAUGCCUAGAGUAGGCACAUAGUGACAGAAAAAUACUUUGCAAGACAAACAGGAAAAAAAAGAGAGAAAGGAAGGGAAACAAGUGAGGGGGAGCCAGCUUCUGACAGACACAAAAUCACUGUGGGAUGAUAAAACAGCCUUAAAUAUAAGAAAUCCAUUACAUACAUAGACACGCACAUGCAUAGAAAGCCACACAAAAUAAUACUUACAACAAGAUUAAGCAGUAAUUUGAGCACUAAUCAAUUACAUGAAGAAACAGUUCAACCAUCAUGUUUCCAAGAUAGAGUUCCCCAAAAGGGACACUAAUUUAAAUUGUACCUGGUAGGAUUAUGCCAGUUGGAGACAUACACACAUAAGUUAAACUUAAAAGUAAGCAGGAAUUUGACCUGAAAGGUCAAAAGAACUGAUAAGAGCACAUGAAAAUUUUGCUGGGGCAACCUCUUAAGAACCUGGUUUAAGACCAGGUUGAGCAUGGUGAAACCCUGUCUCUCCUAAAAUACAAAAAUUAGCUGGGCAUGGUGGCAUGUGCCUGUAAUCACAGCUACUUGGGAGGCUGAGGCAGGGGAAUCACUUGAACUCGGGAGGCGGAGGUUGCAGUGAGCUGAGAUCGUGCCACUGCACUCCAGCCUGGGGACAGAGCAAGACUCCGUCUCAAAAAAAAAAAAGACCAGGUUGGGGGCCUGACAAACCCUCUACCUCCAAGCAAAAUAAAACUAAGUGGAACAAAUGAAGACAAGAUUGAGAAAGGUUUUGAAAAGGUAAUCAAAGUAAUUUGUCUAAAGGACAUCAAGAACUUCUGAACUCCUGAGUCUUUAGAACUAUACCUCUUAGUGACUCAGAGAGUGACAAAAACAAACAGUAGUGUCCUAAGUAACAGAGCAGGUUUCUCAUCACGGAUAAGUGGAUUUGAAGUUGAUUAAAUAAUCAAAGGAUUACUUAAAAAGCAUUCUCAUUCCUAAGAGGCAGAAACUUUGUAUUUGAGAGACUGACAAAAAUAAAUUUAGACCCAAAGCAGGAUUUUCCUCACUUUUGCAGUCAGACAGACCCCUGAAUGGGGGAGACUUAUGAGGCCUCAGAGAAACAUGUUUCAGACAGAGGAGCUCGUGCAGAUCGGUUUCAAUUCACCCCGUGUUAUAGCUCUACAAUUUUUUCACUGUUGAUGCCACAAAAGACCAGAAUGAAAAAAAUCUGUUGAUUGAACAAAGCUAGGUAUGUUAGAUCCCAUGCAAUAAAAAAAGAACACUACAUUAACAAAGUUUCUGUAAGUCUCUAAAUGGGAAAAUUAAGGGAAGAUAUUUUGUAAGAUGUUAAAAUCCAGGCUGGGUUAGUUAAAGAGAGGUAUUGCAAGGUUGAGAAUAGGCAGGGAUUAGGCAGAUUUUAUGACAUUGUAGCUUCGUACAGCAAGGUUAGAGUUUGUGAUUUCAGGGUUCUGAAAUGAAGCAUAUUUUUCUUGUUUAUGUCUUUUCUUUUUAAUCUGGAUAUAAGUAAGAUUUUGUAGCUUUACAGCGGAUUUUACAAAGAGAUGAGGACCAAGAAGGAUUACAGUAGAAGGAUUUUGACUUUUGAAUCAAUAUGCAUUUAGAUGUCGUUUUUAUAAGGCACAUAAGUUAUUUUUAGAAUCAGUUAAACCUUGGAGAUAUUUUUAUUUGAAAAGGCAAAAAACAAAUGAUAAUAUUUAUUUUGCUUCAUCACAUAUUUAUUUGAAAGUAUAUUCAUAAACAAACUUACAGUGUUUUUGUGUGUGCAACUGAUCAUGUAAUUAUUUCUUGCUCUUUAACUAUGUCAAUUAAUAUAAAAGAAAAUACUACUCCAGAUGGUUGAACUGAUUCAGCCUGCUUUUAUCAGAAAAGUAUUUAUUCAUAUCCAAAUGAGGUUGAACUCUUAUGAUUCCCUUCUUAAUUACAAAUAGAAGCUAAUUGCCACCUCAAAAAUAUAGAGAAGAAAACAAACAUUUUCAUUAUUUGAUACUUAUCAUAUCAUAGUAAGAUUUUUUUUCUGUUUUGGUUUAUAUUUUCAUAUUGAACAAAUAAUCCUUGUGUAAACUAUCUACACUUUUUAAUUUUUGGCAUUGCUGUGUAACGUAUUUAGUUCCUGUAAACCCACAACGGAAAAACACUGCUCUUCUCUGGAGAACUUUGCUGCCCUUCUCUCAGCUUGGAAAUAGAUCUCCAAAUUUCUUCCCAUUCCUUAGUCAUCUCUCCUUCGAGGUCAUUUAUUUGACAUUAGGUCCAUUCUCUGUUCACAUCCUAUCCUCCAAGCACUUUGAAACAAUCUCCAGCCAUUGGUCGUCACUCAGCCCCAUGAAAGAUGAGCACUUCUGAUGAGUUUUUACCAUUGUCCUUUAAUCAUACCAAAGGGGCCCCUCAGUUCCUUCCCAGUGAUCACCACAUCCUCACCUAUAUGUCAUCGGAACCUUUUAAAUAAGAUUACCUAAUAAUGAAAAAAAUGCAUUUCUAAUUUUUUAGCUCCUAAGAAACAUUGUGUUGUCAAACUAUUAUAUAAACAAUUGUCUCAAUUAGAUUAAAAUCCAAGAAUUAGAGACUGUUGCAGGAAGUCAGGGACCCCGAAUGGAGGGACUGGCUGGAACUGUGGCAGAGGAACAUAAAUCAUGAUAAUUUCAUGGACGUUUAUCAGUUCCCAAAUAAUACUUUUAUAAUUUCUUAUGCCUGUCUUUAAUCUCUUAAUCCUGUUAUCUUCGUAAGCUGAGGAUGUAUGUCACCUCAGGACCACUGUGAUAAUUAUGUUAACUGUACAAAUUGAUUGUAAAACGUGUGUUUGAACAAUAUGAAAUCAGUGAACCUUGAAAAAGAAGAGAAUAACAGCGAUUUUUAGGGAACAAGGAAAGACAACCAUAAGGUGUGACUGCCUGCGGGGUCGGGCAAAAAGAGCCAUAUUUUUCUUGUUGCAGAGAGCCUAUAAAUGGAUAUGCAAGUAGGAGAGAUAUCACUAAAUUCUUUUCCUAGCAAGGAAUAUUAAUAUUAAUACCCUGGGAAAGGAAUGCAUUCCUGGGGGGAGGUCUAUAAACGGCCGCUCUGGGAAUGUCUGUCUUAUGCAUUUGAGAUAAGGACUGAGAUAAGCCCUGGUCUCCUGCAGUACCCUUAGGCUUACUAGGGUUGGGAAACUCUGCCCUGGUAAUUUUGUGGUCAGAUCGGUUCUCUGCACUUGAACCCUGUUUUCUGUUGUUUAAAAUGUUUAUCCAGACAAUAUAUGCACCACUGAACAUAGCCCUUUAUCAGUAGUUCUGCUUUGCCCUUUGCUUUGUGAUUUUUGUUGGACCCUUAUCGGUAGUUCUGCUUUUUGCCCUUUGAAGCAUGUGAUAUUUGUACCUACUCCGUGUGCUUACACUGCCUCCCCUUUUCAAACCCUUAAUAAAAACUUGCUGGUUUUGAGGCUCAGGUGGGCAUCACGGUCCUACCGAUAUGUGAUGUCACCCCUGGCAGCCCAGCUGUAAAAUUCCUCUCUUUGUACUAUCUCUCUUUAUUUCCCAGCUGGCCAACACUUAUGGAAAAUAGACAGAACCUAUGUUGAAAUAUUGGGGGUGGGUUCCCCCAGUAAGAGACUUUCAGUCUUAUACAAGUCAUAGUUGUGUUCAAAAUAAUAGCUUUAAGUAGAAUUGCUACUAUACACUACAUUUGUCUGCUCAAGCUGCUAUAACAAAUUACCACCAAGUAGGUGACUUUAACAGCAUCAUUUUAAUUUUUCACAGUUCUGGAGGCUAGAAAUCUUUUAUGCCAGCUCAAAAUCAGCAGGUUUAGUUUCUCCUCAAGCCUCCCUUCUUGGCUUGCAGAUGACCACCUUCUUGCUGUGUUCUCACAUGCUCUUUACUCUGCUUAUCCCUGGUGUCCCUUUGUGUGUCUAAAUUUCCUAAUAAGGGCAAUAAUCAGAUAGGAUUAGAGCCCAGCCUAACAGCCUCAUUUUAUUUUUCUUUUUGGUAUAAAUUCAUGUGGUACAGGUGUAAUUUUGUUACAUGCAUAGAUUGUGUGGUGGUGAAGUCAGGGCUUUUAGGGUAUCCUUCACCUGAAUAAUAUACAUUGUACCCAUUAAGUAAUUUCUCAUCAUCCACCUACCUCCUACCCUCUUACCCUUCUGAAUCUCCAUUGUCUAUCAUUUCACUCUUUACCUUCAUAUAGAGUUUAGCUCCCACUUAUAUGAUAGAACAUGAAGUAUUUCUUUUCUGUGUCAGAUAAUUAUCCUUCAAAAGCCUUAUCCCCAAAUAUAACCACAUUAGGAGGUCCUGGGGGAUAGGGCUUUACCGUAUAAAUUAGGGGAGGACAUAACAUACACUACAAGUAAUAUGACUACAUCAUCUGUUUCCCUCAAAAAAAGGGCUUCCUCUUUGCCCUCUGCUAUUUACCCAAGAGCUUCUUGUUCUCUUCAAUAACUUUGAAACUUGAUCACAUUCAAAUUCCAACCACUAACAGUAAACAAAAAAAAAAAAAAAUAGGCCAGGCACAGUGGCUCAUGCCUGUAAUCCCAGCACUUUGGGAGGCAGAGGUGGGCGGAUCACAAGGUCAGGAGUUUGAGACCAGCCUAGCCAAUAUGGUGAAACCCCAUCUCUACUAAAAAUAUAAACAUUAGCCAGGUGUGGUGGUGGAUGCCUAUAGUCCCAGCUACUCAGGAGGCAGAGGCAGGGGAAUCGCUUGAACCUGGGAGGAGGAAGUUGCAGUGAGAUGAGAUCACACCACUACACUCCAGCCUGGGUGACAGAGUGAGAAUCCAUCUCAAAAAAAUAAAUAAAAAUAACAAAAUAAAAAUAAAAUAACCCUUGUAAACAGUUCCCUGUCUGCAAUUAUGAUAUUCCAAGUGCUCUGAAAACUGGUUUAUUUUUUCCUCAAAGGGAGGCUCAAGCUAGUUUGAUGGUAAAAACCUGUCCUAAACUAAAAGACCUACUUACGGUUUUUGUUUUUUUUUCACUUCACAUGAACAUUUAUAUGUUUUGCUGCAGAAACAUCAAAGUGUUUUGUACAGCCUGCUGCUCCAAACCUUACUGGGGAUAUUUUUAAAAUGUGGUAAAUGCUCUGUAUUAUUAUCUGAUAAUCAAAGUAAUUCUGAAUUACCAGAUACAUUUGACCUUCAGAAUGUUAGAUAAGGAAUUGUAGGACUGUGGCAAGAUACAUUUCACUCUGAACACUAGAAAAACAGGGUCCUGUCUCUUCGCCAUAAAAAAUGAGUUAGCAUUUACUAUGUGCUUAUCAUGGGCCAGGUGUUGUUGUAAGCACUUUACACAUAUUCAAUCAUUUAAUUCUCCAGUAAACUUUAGAAAUAGUCACGAUUAUUCUCAUUUUAAUACAGAAGAAAUGAAAUCAGAAAGUGUUUGAAUAACUUUCCCGAAGUCAUAGUUAGUAAGCCCAGGAAGCCAGAAUUCAAAGCUAGAAAAUAUGUCUCCAGUGUAAAACUUAAACAAUACACUAUGACUUAUAAGGAGAGAAAUUAAUAGACAUACCACAACUGAAUAAUUCUGGACUAAUGGCAUUCCUUGAGAGCAUUAACUAAUCUCCACUUAACUAAACACUUCUAUUCUCUCUCCCUCUUUUUCUACUCUUUCCCAUGGUCUGUCUAUCUUGCCUACCUAUUCAUUGCCUAUAGGUGUUAUCUCAUCCAAGACAUGACUAUAACUACUAUUUUGAUGUGCUUUGGAAUUGUUGGAUUACAAAGAAUAGAAACUUAUGUGUCAGGUGCAUCCAUUUGGUCUUGGUCUCUGUCUUUUGGAAAAUGGACAGUUAUUUAUUCUAUUUCUCUUUUCUCAAAUUCCACACCACUGUACUCUGUGCAAGCUAGAUAGCCUCUUUACUUUUUUUGUUUGUACUUUGUCCUCCAUGAUAACCUCCAAAUGAUGGUAUCAGCUAUCUACUCUAUAGAUGAAUUAUAACUUCUAAUUAUUGACAAUGUGGUAUAAUUUUCCCAGGUUCAGCUACAUGAUUCAAUCAAAUAUAGCCGUGUGCCACAGAAUGACAUUUUGCCCAAGGAUAGACUGCAUAGAUGACAGUGGUUUCAUAAGACUGUAAUGGGGCUACCCUAUACUGGUGUAUUUUUUUUAUCUUUGAUAACAUAUUUUCACUGUAGCUUUUCUCUGUUUAGAUAUGCUUAGAUACACAAAUAUUUAACACUGUGUUACAGUUGUCUACAGUAUUGAGUCUAAUAACAUGCUGUACAUGUUUGUAGCCUGAGAACAAUAGGCUAUACCGCAUAGCCUAGGUGUAUAGUAGCCUAUGCCAUCUAGGUUUGUGUAAGUCGAAUCUUUGAUGUUCACACAAUAAUAAAAUCACCUGACAAUGCAUUUCUUUUUUCAUUUGAGACAGAGCCCCGCUCUGUCACCCAGGCUGGAGUGCAGUGGCGUGAUCUUGGCUCACUGCAACCUCCACCUCCCAGGUUCAAGUGAUUCUCCUGCCUCAGCCUCCUGAGUAUCUGGGACUGCAGGCGCAUGCUACCACGCCUGGCUAAUUUUUUUGUAUUUUUAGUAGAGAUGGGGUUUCACCAUGUGAGUCAGGAUGGUCUGAAUCUCCUGACCUCGUGAUCCACCCGCCUUGGCCUCCCAUAGUGCUGGGAUUACAGGCAUCAAUGCAUUUCUUAGAAUGUAUUCCCUUGGUUAAGCAAUGCAUGAUGGUAAUUAUGCUUUAGUAACAGGAAUUUGUUUAAGAAAAAGGCAUUUUCUUUUUCUCUUUUUUUUUUUUUUUUUGAUGUUUGAAAAGAAGAAAAAAUUCGAAUGAUAAAAGCACCAUUUAGCCUAUCUUUUACAUUUACCACCAGUAAUAUAAUAGAAGAUUCUCAUGAUCUGGAAAUAUUGUGUGUGGGAAAGACAUUAAGGCACUGUGGUUAGGGAAGUUAUGUCAGUAAUAGCCCUUCUAGAAUUAAGGUUGGGCAGUGCUGGGCUACCAUUUCCAUUUUCUUUUGUUAUUUUUUGAUCAGUAGGGAUUGAGUGAGGAAAAUAAGAAAUUUGCCUGAAACAAGCAGUUUGUAGACUCUAUCAGCUUUUCCUUUUGAUUUUCUCUUGAUUUCUGCCAUACCGAUGUCCUGACCAUCAUUGAAAAGUUAGCUUCUCAGUUAUCCAAGUAGACAUCCAAGUCUAUUUCAGUGAAGUGAGGUGAAAGUCUUAUCUUUCAUUGAUUAAAAGCAACUAACCCUAUGAAGAGAGACAAAUGUUAACAAUAUAGUAAAUUAAAACAGUUCUCUAUAUAUUACUGAUCCAAUGUAUAUCUAAUCCAUUGUAUUUCUUAAAUCAAAUCAUUGCCAAUAUGUGAUUCCUGAUUGUGGCCUGUAAAUCUCUUUUGUAAGCUAUAGAGACAGGGAUCAGAUAAUAUUCUGCAAAUGAAAAUUCACAAUAUAUUUGCUUGUCCAUUUCUAUAUGGCAUUGGGGUAGAUAGUCACAAAUAGAACUUUGAAGAGUAUCCUCUAAAAUGGUUGAGAGAAAAUAUAUGGCUUAUUCGAAUUUGUAUUUUUAUUUGUAAUUACUCAGAAUGUUAGAUUAAAAAUGAGCAAGUUAAUGAAAUACAGCAAUUUUAACUCAUCUGCCUAUUAACUGAUACCAUUGUCAAACCAAAUCAUAAGUGUUCUCCUAUGCUUUAUAUAAAAAUAAAUUGAAAUGCAGAUUUACUUUAUACUCUGACGUAUAGUACUUAAAAAAUUUAACAUAUUUGUUGAAACACAAGCAGUCAAUUUUAAGGUUCUGUGCAUACUGUAUACAACCUGUUAGCCUCUUUUUUAUCAAAAAUAGACAAGUGUUUCUUUAUUCAUUUCUUGCUUCCAAUGGUGGCCUAUCAAAACUGUUGCUUUCUCCUCUGACAAGUUAUAUUUAGUAACUGUGAUGGUUAAUUUUAGGUGUCAACUUGACUAGAUCAAGGAAUACGAAGAUAGCUGGUAAAGUAUUAUUUUUGGGUAUGUCUGCGAGGGUGUUUCUAGAGAAGAUUGGCAUUUGAAUCAGUAGACUGAAUAAGGAAGAUCUGCCCUCACCCAGUGUGGGUGGGCACCAUCAAAUCAGCUGAGGACUCAGAUAGAAUGAAAAGGCAGAAGAAAGGCAGAUUUGCUUUCUCUGUUCCGGAGCUGGGGCACCCUUCUUCUCUUGCCUUGGACAUCAGAACUCCAGAUUCUCUGGCCCUUGGACUCUGACUUGUAGCAACACCCCCACCCCAUUCUUAGGCAUUUAGCCUUGGACUGAGAGUUACAGCAUCCAUUUCCCUAGUCCUGAGGCCUUUGGACUAGGACUGAGCCAUACUAUUGGCUUCCCUUAUUCUCCAGGUCACAGACAGACUAGCAAGGGUCUUCUCAAGCUCGAUGAUUUCUUCAGCUAGUUCCCCUAAUAUAUCCCCUCUCAUCUAUCUAUCUAUUGAUUGAUGUAUCAAUCUAUCAUGUAUCUACCUACCUACCUUUCUACCUACCCACCACCUUAUCUAACCUGUCUCCUAAAUGUUCUAUCUCUCCAGAGAAACCUAACUAAUACAGUAACUUAUUAGCCCUAGUAUAUUUUCUGGAAGCAAAGGUCCCAAAGAUUAUUGAGGGUAGGUAGUCCUAAGUUAAAAAAAAAAAGUGUCAAAAGUGUAGAGAGAUCAAAAGCAUUAAGUAAAGCAAAUUAUCUUCCAAUUUUGCCUUGAAAAGAAUAUGACUUUUUUAAUGAAUGACUUUUGAUGGAAUAAAACAGGUGAUAGUCAUGUUGAAAAUAAUAGUUCAAGAGUUGGCAACAAGAAAAUGAAUGUGAAAAGUGUAUUUAAGAAUAUGGCAAAUAAAGGAAUUUAAAACAACUAGAUGCUACCUGGAGAAUAUAGUAACUUCAAUAUUCAUUUCAGAGUAAUUCAUAAAUGUUUUAAUGUAGAACUCCAGUCAAAUAAAACUGCUAAGAUUUAGGCAUUAAUGGAGCCCAUGGUUUCACAAAGGGUCAUAAAAUAAUUUAUUAGAAUUUUGUAUAUGUUGUAUUGUUUUUCAGACAAAGACAUCUAUGACACAAAAAUUCAUUAAAUUAUCUCAAAACCAAAGAAUGAUUAUAUAAUAGAAGGCAGGAUAGUAUAUUAAACUUUUUAUAUAGCACGUAUUUUGGAGCUUCUUAUACAAGUUCUGCCCUUUGCUUAGAUUAAAACUAAGCAAAUUAAAGAAAUUUAGCAAUUUUAACUCAUCUACCUGUUAUCUGACACCAUUGCCAAACCAUAUCAUCAGUGUUGUCCUAUGCUUGGUUAUGUAAAAACUUAGUGAAAUGUAGAUUUACUUUAUAUUCUAGAAAAAUGGAAUUUAAAAAAAAAUUAACACAUUUGUUGAGACACAUGGAGUCAGUGAGCAAUGUGAUGUUGAACAAGUUGCCUAUCUUUUCAUAUUUCAGUUGUUUCUUCACUAGGAAAAAAAUAAACUUAGUGCUUGCUCCUUAUAGGAUUGUUAUGAAUAGAUAAAAUAAAAUUGCCUAUAAAAAUGAUGACCUCAAUAUCUGGUACCAAUAAAAAUACUCACUAGGAAAGUUUUAAAUACUGUUGUUUCUGUUACUUCACUUUGAAUUAAUAAGACAGUAGACAUUCUACUCACUAAGUGUAAAGCCACUUACUCAACACCACAUCCCACACUGAAUAGUGGCCUAUUCACGGAGAAACUUCUCAGGAAUUACUAGUUGCAAAAAUAGUACUUGACACUUAUUUCUGUAAUAUUGUGCUUAUCACAUUGUACUGUGACUUUUUGUUUAUCUCUGUCAGUCUGUCAAAUAGACUAUGAGUUCCUAGAGAACAAUGUUUUAUUCAACUUAUAUUCAUAAAACCUAGUAUGGCUUCUAAUAUGUAGUAAGUACCCAAUAAAUGUUUGUUGAGUUGAA